AGAUUCACUGGUGUGGCAAGUUGUCUCUCAGACUGUACAUGCAUUAAAAUUUUGCUUGGCAUUACUCAAAAGCAAAAGAAAAGUAAAAGGAAGAAACAAGAACAAGAAAAAAGAUUAUAUUGAUUUUAAAAUCAUGCAAAAACUGCAACUCUGUGUUUAUAUUUACCUGUUUAUGCUGAUUGUUGCUGGUCCAGUGGAUCUAAAUGAGAACAGUGAGCAAAAAGAAAAUGUGGAAAAAGAGGGGCUGUGUAAUGCAUGUACUUGGAGACAAAACACUAAAUCUUCAAGAAUAGAAGCCAUUAAGAUACAAAUCCUCAGUAAACUUCGUCUGGAAACAGCUCCUAACAUCAGCAAAGAUGUUAUAAGACAACUUUUACCCAAAGCUCCUCCACUCCGGGAACUGAUUGAUCAGUAUGAUGUCCAGAGGGAUGACAGCAGCGAUGGCUCUUUGGAAGAUGACGAUUAUCACGCUACAACGGAAACAAUCAUUACCAUGCCUACAGAGUCUGAUUUUCUAAUGCAAGUGGAUGGAAAACCCAAAUGUUGCUUCUUUAAAUUUAGCUCUAAAAUACAAUACAAUAAAGUAGUAAAGGCCCAACUAUGGAUAUAUUUGAGACCCGUCGAGACUCCUACAACAGUGUUUGUGCAAAUCCUGAGACUCAUCAAACCUAUGAAAGACGGUACAAGGUAUACUGGAAUCCGAUCUCUGAAACUUGACAUGAACCCAGGCACUGGUAUUUGGCAGAGCAUUGAUGUGAAGACAGUGUUGCAAAAUUGGCUCAAACAACCUGAAUCCAACUUAGGCAUUGAAAUAAAAGCUUUAGAUGAGAAUGGUCAUGAUCUUGCUGUAACCUUCCCAGGACCAGGAGAAGAUGGGCUGAAUCCGUUUUUAGAGGUCAAGGUAACAGACACACCAAAAAGAUCCAGAAGGGAUUUUGGUCUUGACUGUGAUGAGCACUCAACAGAAUCACGAUGCUGUCGUUACCCUCUAACUGUGGAUUUUGAAGCUUUUGGAUGGGAUUGGAUUAUCGCUCCUAAAAGAUAUAAGGCCAAUUACUGCUCUGGAGAGUGUGAAUUUGUAUUUUUACAAAAAUAUCCUCAUACUCAUCUGGUACACCAAGCAAACCCCAGAGGUUCAGCAGGCCCUUGCUGUACUCCCACAAAGAUGUCUCCAAUUAAUAUGCUAUAUUUUAAUGGCAAAGAACAAAUAAUAUAUGGGAAAAUUCCAGCGAUGGUAGUAGACCGCUGUGGGUGCUCAUGAGAUUUAUAUUAAGCGUUCAUAACUUCCUAAAACAUGGAAGGUUUUCCCCUCAACAAUUUUGAAGCUGUGAAAUUAAGUACCACAGGCUAUAGGCCUAGAGUAUGCUACAGUCACUUAAGCAUAAGCUACAGUAUGUAAACUAAAAGGGGGAAUAUAUGCAAUGGUUGGCAUUUAACCAUCCAAACAAAUCAUACAAGAAAGUUUUAUGAUUUCCAGAGUUUUUGAGCUAGAAGGAGAUCAAAUUACAUUUAUGUUCCUAUAUAUUACAACAUCGGCGAGGAAAUGAAAGCGAUUCUCCUUGAGUUCUGAUGAAUUAAAGGAGUAUGCUUUAAAGUCUAUUUCUUUAAAGUUUUGUUUAAUAUUUACAGAAAAAUCCACAUACAGUAUUGGUAAAAUGCAGGAUUGUUAUAUACCAUCAUUCGAAUCAUCCUUAAACACUUGAAUUUAUAUUGUAUGGUAGUAUACUUGGUAAGAUAAAAUUCCACAAAAAUAGGGAUGGUGCAGCAUAUGCAAUUUCCAUUCCUAUUAUAAUUGACACAGUACAUUAACAAUCCAUGCCAACGGUGCUAAUACGAUAGGCUGAAUGUCUGAGGCUACCAGGUUUAUCACAUAAAAAACAUUCAGUAAAAUAGUAAGUUUCUCUUUUCUUCAGGUGCAUUUUCCUACACCUCCAAAUGAGGAAUGGAUUUUCUUUAAUGUAAGAAGAAUCAUUUUUCUAGAGGUUGGCUUUCAAUUCUGUAGCAUACUUGGAGAAACUGCAUUAUCUUAAAAGGCAGUCAAAUGGUGUUUGUUUUUAUCAAAAUGUCAAAAUAACAUACUUGGAGAAGUAUGUAAUUUUGUCUUUGGAAAAUUACAACACUGCCUUUGCAACACUGCAGUUUUUAUGGUAAAAUAAUAGAAAUGAUCGACUCUAUCAAUAUUGUAUAAAAAGACUGAAACAAUGCAUUUAUAUAAUAUGUAUACAAUAUUGUUUUGUAAAUAAGUGUCUCCUUUUUUAUUUACUUUGGUAUAUUUUUACACUAAGGACAUUUCAAAUUAAGUACUAAGGCACAAAGACAUGUCAUGCAUCACAGAAAAGCAACUACUUAUAUUUCAGAGCAAAUUAGCAGAUUAAAUAGUGGUCUUAAAACUCCAUAUGUUAAUGAUUAGAUGGUUAUAUUACAAUCAUUUUAUAUUUUUUUACAUGAUUAACAUUCACUUAUGGAUUCAUGAUGGCUGUAUAAAGUGAAUUUGAAAUUUCAAUGGUUUACUGUCAUUGUGUUUAAAUCUCAACGUUCCAUUAUUUUAAUACUUGCAAAAACAUUACUAAGUAUACCAAAAUAAUUGACUCUAUUAUCUGAAAUGAAGAAUAAACUGAUGCUAUCUCAACAAUAACUGUUACUUUUAUUUUAUAAUUUGAUAAUGAAUAUAUUUCUGCAUUUAUUUACUUCUGUUUUGUAAAUUGGGAUUUUGUUAAUCAAAUUUAUUGUACUAUGACUAAAUGAAAUUAUUUCUUACAUCUAAUUUGUAGAAACAGUAUAAGUUAUAUUAAAGUGUUUUCACAUUUUUUUGAAAGACA